ACUCAUUGCACCUUCCUGCCACCCCAGGCAGUGUCUGGGCCCUCAGCUCCCCCUCCCUCCACCUACCCCCUCACACCCACCACUACGACCCCACGGGAUACCCAGCCCAGACGGAGGAAACACCGAGCCUAGAGACAUGAGAGUUGGAGGAGCAUUCCACCUUCUACUCGUGUGCCUGAGCCCAGCACUGCUGUCUGCUGUGCGGAUCAACGGGGAUGGACAGGAGGUCCUGUACCUGGCAGAAGGUGAUAAUGUGAGGCUGGGCUGCCCCUACGUCCUGGACCCUGAGGACUAUGGUCCCAAUGGGCUGGACAUCGAGUGGAUGCAGGUCAACUCAGACCCCGCCCACCACCGAGAGAACGUGUUCCUUAGUUACCAGGACAAGAGGAUCAACCAUGGCAGCCUUCCCCAUCUGCAGCAGAGGGUCCGCUUUGCAGCCUCAGACCCAAGCCAGUACGAUGCCUCCAUCAACCUCAUGAACCUGCAGGUAUCUGAUACAGCCACUUAUGAGUGCCGGGUGAAGAAGACCACCAUGGCCACCCGGAAGGUCAUUGUCACUGUCCAAGCACGACCUGCAGUGCCCAUGUGCUGGACAGAGGGCCACAUGACAUAUGGCAACGAUGUGGUGCUGAAGUGCUAUGCCAGUGGGGGCUCCCAGCCCCUCUCCUACAAGUGGGCCAAGAUCAGUGGGCACCAUUACCCCUAUCGAGCUGGGUCUUACACCUCCCAGCACAGCUACCACUCAGAGCUGUCCUACCAGGAGUCCUUCCACAGCUCCAUAAACCAAGGCCUGAACAAUGGGGACCUGGUGUUGAAGGAUAUCUCCAGAGCAGAUGAUGGGCUGUAUCAGUGCACAGUGGCCAACAACGUGGGCUACAGUGUUUGUGUGGUGGAGGUGAAGGUCUCAGACUCCCGGCGUAUAGGCGUGAUCAUCGGCAUCGUCCUGGGCUCUCUGCUCGCGCUGGGCUGCCUGGCCGUAGGCAUCUGGGGGCUCGUCUGCUGCUGCUGCGGGGGCUCCGGGGCUGGCGGCGCCCGCGGUGCCUUCGGCUACGGCAACGGCGGCGGGGUCGGCGGAGGGGCCUGCGGCGACUUGGCUAGUGAGAUCAGAGAGGACGCCGUGGCGCCCGGGUGCAAGGCCAGCGGGCGCGGCAGCCGCGUCACCCACCUCCUGGGGUACCCGACGCAGAACGUCAGCCGCUCCCUGCGCCGCAAGUACGCGCCUCCCCCCUGCGGCGGCCCCGAGGACGUGGCCCUGGCGCCCUGCACCGCCGCCGCCGCCUGCGAAGCGGGCCCCUCCCCGGUCUACGUCAAGGUCAAGAGCGCGGAGCCGGCUGACUGCGCCGAGGGGCCGGUGCAGUGCAAGAACGGCCUCUUGGUGUGAGCGCGCGCGCCGGGCCGGGCUGCGCCCCAGCCAGGAGGAGGGCGCGGGGCUCUCUGUCUGCAGCUGGGGACACGUCGGGGCUGGGGACGACCUCGCUCGCCCCAGGCUGCCAGGCGGCUGGGGGUGAAGGCAUUUCCCUAAGGAAAUGCGUAGGGAGGCAGAGCCUCCUCCCCAAAAGUGGGAAGGGGCGGGCGAGGGCGGAGGAAGGCGAUCCUGAGCCUUCUCCGCACCCCCGGGACCGAAGGCUUGGGGGAGAGGGAGGGAGGAGGAGGCUGAGUGUCCUAGAGCGGCUGAGGCCGGAGGCCUGGUGUCCCCAGCCUAAGCAGAGGGCCCCGGGGGCCGGGUGGGUGGGGGUCUGUCUGGACGAAUUGUUCUGUGUGUGAGGUCUGAGCUCUGAGGCAGCAGUGUUAGCACAAUAAAGAAACAUUGAGACGUGA